CUCUGUAGCAGAAACUGAGCUCCGGGUGGCUGGUUCUCAGUGGUUGUCUCAUGUCUCUUUUUCUGUCUUAGGUGGUUUCAUUAAAUGCAGCACUUGGUUAGCAGAUGUUUAAUUUUUUUUUUAACAACAUUAACUUGUGGCCUCUUUCUACACCUGGAAAUUUACUCUUGAAUAAAUAAAAACUCGUUUGUCUUGUCUUCUGCAUGUGGGCUGUGGUCUUCUCCUGCUCCUUUCAGGGUACAUUCUGCUAGAACCAUGGAAGGCAGGCCCCCAGUUCCGUGGUCCCAGAGUGCACUGAAGACAUGACUUUUUCAGAAACUCUUUUUCCUCCUUUUUGUCCAGUAAGACCAUAUCUAUUUUAUAUAAAAUGGCCUUGUUUUGCUUUAUUUGACACAAUCUUAUACCACCAAGCAUGCUCGAAAGAAGCAGUGAAAGUAAAAAUCACCUAGUUGAAUAAUAACGCCUGAAAGGUUGAAGGAACUGAAUUUGGUGGGGAGGGCAGGUAGGGGUUAGGGAUUACAGGUUAGGAUGAGGCAUGGUGAUCUUUUGGGAACACUGCUGUGAAGAAAGCCUAGAAGCUUAAAAAUGAAAUGUGAAGUUGUAGCAAGUAAUGGCUAAAUUAAUUAAAUCUUGGAGUUUCCUAUCUUAAAGUACAAGUAUAAUCAUGGGCAUAUAUUUUGCCACCUAUUUUGAGUCAGUAUACUAGCAGUCAGCUCUUAGGUGGUACAGGGAUUACAACCCCAUUCACAAUUGAGUUGAAUAACAUGGACCUUAGGUCAUCCAUUGUUAGGGCAAAAGGAAGGAACAUUCAUACAAAGUGCUUGUGAGCAAGUGAUUGAUUUGAUCCAGUUCUUUUCAUCCCACUAAUUUCACUAGACCCUUGGAUUUCUUUGGUCUGUGAGUUUCCCAGGAAAACCACCAGGGGACAGUGAUGGAUCAGGAAUACAGUUAUCAACAGCCAAGCUUUCCUAGUUAAUGCUAGGAGCCAGUCAACCAGUGUACUUUUUACCUAAGAUCUUUUGUGUAUCCUGCCACAUUGAGUCUAGAGUGACAGUCCACCUUGUCUCCCAUACCAGACUCUAGAUGUAUCAGAAUUGUGUGAAUUCCUGAGGCUGUUAACUGUUGUGCGGGUCUCUGGCUUCGGACUGCCUAUGGUUGAAUCCUGGCACCAACAAUUAACAGGACUACCAGUGUGAUCUUGAAAUCACUUCAUCUCUCUGUGUGUCAGUCUCCUUAUCUGUUAAAUAGGACUAAUAAUAAUAGGGCUGUGAAGACUAAAUGAGAUGAGGCAUGUAAAACACUUAGAAUGACCCUGGCUAUAGUAUAUACUCUCUAAAUGUUAGCUGUCACUCUGGGAGACAGACAUUCUUCUUUGUCUACAAAUAGCAGGAAAAUUAGAAGGUUCAAUCUGAGAUUUGAUGAUGUCUCCUCAGAAGGAUGAGGCUAUCCUCUGUGCACAAGAACUUUCUGAAAGGCCUGGAAAAGCUCAAUUCUCAUGUGUCCACUGUCUCCCUAUUCCCAGAAGAUUUCUCAUGCCAUUUAGCUCCUUUGAAGUUAACAGCUACCCACCCUGCAUACUCCUCUGCCCUUGUGUUAAAAGAAGACAGGACUCACAAUACCAUGCAAAAUGAGUACUUGCCUCUAGCUAGGAACAGUGCCUACUUCAGGGAGAAUUGAUUUUGAUACAGCUGACUAGUUUGAGUGUUAAACUAUUUUGGAAAUAAUUUACAUAUCUAAGUUCUAAAAUAUAUUUUUCUUUCCUCCACUUAUUCUUCAAAUUUGAAACAAUGUUUUAAUACUGUAUAUCUUUCAUUGUUUAUAACUUGCAUUCUUUGUGAAAAUUUGUUCUUAGGGACAAAAAAAUUCUUAAUCUUUUUAUGUGUAAAGCAGGAACAGACAGAUAAUACAUAAACAGAUACAUAUUAUAUCUGCGGUAUUAAAAUUUGGUGGGGUGGUCGAUUAGGAUUAAAAGGUCCAUAAAAGCUCCUGUAAGGAGUGAUAAUGAAAAGGGUGGGGAAGCACUAAAGACAAAGAGUAUAAGUAGAUAUUUCAGAAAUCGAAAUUAAAAAGUAUUUCGGCUAGUUUAUACCCUUCCAUCAGAGCAAAAGGGGAACACAACAGCUUGUGACUGUUUGCCAGCCAUCGCGGGGCUACAUGAAGCCUGCAGCCGUGAGCUAGGUAGGGCUCCCGUGGGGGGAUUAGUUUGAAAGGUCGUCUUCUACAGACAGUUCACAGACGCCCCCGUGAGUCAUUAAAACAUUGAGAAGCACUGAAUCUUAGGUAUAUCAAAAAGGUCAUCCUCUUUCCAAUGACCGUCUCAUGCUUUUCUAGUCCACGGAGCAGGUUUUGGAGGCUCAGCUCUUACAUGAAUUCCAGGACAGAUAAAUCCCAGAUUCUAAUUGUUGAAAUAAUAAUGAGGGGCACCCCUGCUUAUAGAAUAAAGGGAACCCAACACCUCAUAUCUCCAGUUUGGGAAAAGGUUAAAUAUGAAGACUAGUAUUCAGUCAAAUCUUCAUACUAAUAAAAAGCAACAAGCAUGGAGUAAUUUUAAAUCCUGCAUAUUUGGUUUUUAAAUCUUAGUUGACUUUUUUUAAAAGGAACAGAGUGAUCUUUUUUUUUUUUAACACAAAGUCUUUCAGAAAAGAAACAGGGUGAUCUUGAUUAUGCUUUGGAAAGGUUGAUAAAAACAGCUUGUUCUCUGAGAACACCCUCCAGACAUAGGAAGAGUGGCUUGAAAUAGGUGAGGUCAACUAAGAGAAAAUGAUCUGGGAUCAGCCAUUCACUUCAGAUAAUCCAAAAAGCAAUGGUUAAAUGGGUUGGUACAAGGACAGGGUUACAGUAUAUAAGAAAAGCAUUAGCACAGAAAAAGGAGUCGUGUAAGAAAGUCGCCAAGGUGAAAGUCACGUUAAACAAGUGUUUUUCCCAAGGAAGAGACAGAACAGGAAAUAGAGGUUGGGGUAUGCCUUAUUUAAAGGCCUGGAACACUCAGGCGAGGGUGUGUGUGUGUGUGUGUGUGUGUGUGUGUUGGGAAUGGGGCUGGGGGGAGACAGGGUUGUGUGUGUGUGUGUGUGUGUGUGUGUGUGUGUGUGUGUGUGUGUGUGUGUUGGGAAUGGGGCUGGGGGGAGACAGGGUUGAGUGACCCAAAGUAGAAAGUGGCUCUGGAUCUCCACAGAUGUUGCCUGAAAGUCUUUGAAGGAUUUGAGUCAUUUUGGGUGGUUGUGUCUUUUUCUCUGAAGAGAAUUCCUCAGCCUAUCCCUAGAUUCUAAACUGAAUCCGAUUCACUUACAGCUGUCAGUUGACUAGCAACUAAAUGGUCUGGGUGUUGGUUGCCAUGGAAACAGCUAAAAGGCCCAUUGCUAUGGGAACCUACCAGGCUCUCCAAACCAGGGGUUUGGUUCCUAAAAAGGGGUGGAGGGGAGGGUGGAGACCAGGAGAUGGCCUGCAUAGGUGGCUCAAGGGUCCUGGAAGAGGGUGGGCAAUGUGGGUGAGUGGAUCCGGCCAGCUCCUCUCGACUGGGGCAGAAGAACAGUGACCUCUUCUACUUUCUGCAGAUGUUCCCAUGCCUGUUCUCUGCUCACUGCCCAAUGCUAGCCACAGAGCACAGGUGUUUGCAGUUGCAAAUGGAGACUAAGAGCCUGAGAUUCUGGAGCAGACGUGGCAUGUCAGUGUGGCUCCCCUCACCUGCAGGGGCUUGGAGAAGGACGGCUCCCUUCUAGCAGGCCGUCCUCCACAAAUCAUAUGUCCCAGAUAAGCAGCCAGCAGGCAGAAAGAUCAGCUUAGCUCUGACUGCCAGUGGGUAAGGCCAAGAAGGAGCCUGGCAGACAAAUGGAUGGCUGCUGGCCUUGAACAUGGCAGAGCUGCUGGGUGUGCCAGAUCAAAAAGCAGAGAGCAGGCCAGCAGCAGCAGACUGUUCUCAGCGCUGGAGAAAUGCAUUGCUCUGCCCACUACACCCUCAACCAUCCAUAUGCCUCUGCCACAAAGGGGGAUACUGCAAAUGGAUCAACAUAGGAAAGAUGAGGUUUGAUGGAGAUUCUCAGUGUACACACACAAUGCUUGUAAGAUUCUUUUCUGUUUUGCAAUCAAAGUAACUCUCACAUUAGUGUUUAGUGGUAAGAUGAUUUUUUUACUAAAACAAAGAGAAAACAUCCCAGAAGCUCUUCCAUUAACCACUGUUAAUGUGUAAUGUACAAAUUGAAGGGAUUGGACUAAUCACUAAAGCCUCUGUCAGGACUAACAGCUUAUGAUGCAUUGAGACGCUGAAAGGAAGUUGAAGAACCACUGGCAAAUGGACACAGAUGAAUCGUUUUCUAGUUACUCAUAUUGUGAGGGCGGGGAAAAUCUCUGAACUCCAGAGAGGCUUAGGAUGGAGACUAAGGCCAAGACAUUUGCUUUAGAGACCAUUUCAGAUAUGUUGGGCCCAGGAGACUUUCACUUGGUUCUGCAGAAUUCUGAGAUUUGUGAUGCUGAUUUUUUUUUCUCCUAAUCUUGCCUUUUUCCUGCCUGGAAUUGUUAGUCUCAGACCCUCCCAGGAGCUUCAGAGUCUAAGAGCCUGGCACCAGAGAAAGAGAGAGAGAGAGAUGCCACUAGAACUUGGACUGCUCCACAGGACAGUUGAGCACUUCCCCAGAAUCUGUGGGGAGGUUUUCACUUUUGGAAGCAGUAGUUGUUUACAGAUUUCUGUAACAUUUAAAAUGUUAAAUACAAGCUGGGUUUAUAUCUCACCUCCAACUUUUUCCAGCUGCUUGACUUUUGAUGAGUUCCUUAACCUCUUAGGGCCUUAAUUUCCUCAGCUGUAAAACAGGAUGAUAAGAAUAUACCCACCUCAGGUGGUUCUAAUGAUGACAUGAGAUGGGGGAUGCAAAGUGCUCAGUGCAGUACCUGACGCAUAAUAAGUAGCUGAGAAAGGUCGUUAGUAUUAUUAUUAUCAUCCUAGAUAAAAAAGGAAGGUUGCAGCCAUGGAAACUGCUCAGUGGCCUAGAAUCAUAGGCAUUUGCCAUGCAUUUGUCUUCCAAAUUUAAUUCCAGGUGCCUUUCAAGACUGAUGGCCUCUCUGAUGCCACACUCUGGUUUGCCUUCAUUAAGCCAGAUUCUAACCCUCUCUUUUUAAGACACUUAACCACAUUCUUUUUCAUGUAUGAUUUUUAUGUGUCUGCUUACCUUCCUACUAGACUGUAAACAUCUUGAGAAUAGAGACUACCCUUUCAUCUUUCAAUAAAUGCCUAGACCUCAGCAAUUGUUUAAUGAAUUUUUUUAAUAGGGAAAAAUGUCUUUUUUCUGUAGGUCUUGGAUCAGACCAUUUAACCCUAUAGCAGCCUUGUCUCCAAAGGGAAGAAAAGAGUAACAGUGGGCUAGGUUUCAUUCUCCUGAAGAAGGGCACGGCAUUGCCUCAUCCUGAGUGGGCAGCUCCAGAGCAGGGCCAGGGCUCACAUCUUCUAGAAGCCAGCUGUCAUCUGUCUGUAAGAUUCAUUGACACCAGCUUGUCUCCAGCCUGAAGGCUCCCUGGCCCUGGGCUCAGGCAGAAAUGGCUCCUCCUCCCCUCCUGGCUGCUGUCUGUCUUCAGUUCAGCCUGCCUCUCCCUCCUGAUUGCUCUGGCUGAAGCAAGAAGCCAUGAAGAUGGCUCUGUAGCUGCAAGUUGCAUCAGGUUGCCUCUGGGAGAAAGAGAGAAAGCAGACCCGGCUUAUGCAACUCUCUCUCCCCAUACACUGAAUCUCUGAAGUUCCUGGCCAACCCCCUCAGCUUCCCACCAGAGUUUGCCAAGGCUUGGCUUGGCAGGAACAAGGCCCAAAGAGCUACACAGAGCAUCUCCCAGACAGUGGCCACUGAGAACCAUCUCCUGUCAAGGCUCUGAGGACUGCUCAGCUGGCCCAGGCCCCCCUCCCCAGCAGCUGCCCCAGAACCAUGGAGAGUCUGAGUGAACUACAGAACCCGCUGCUGCCCAGGAGCCCUGCCCAUCUCCAUGGCCCCUAUCCCUACCCGGAGACCCCACCCAGCUGGUCCUGCCAGGAAAAGCUCUACUCCUACCUCCUAGGUGGCGCUGGGCCUGCCGGAGCCCACCAGCUCCUGGACCCAGGGUCCCUGCAGCUGGCCGUGGAGGCCUGGUACCGGCCCAGCUGCCUCCUGGGGAGAGACAAGGUCAAGGAGCCCAGGGCAGGCAGCUGUGAGACAAGCUUCACAGAGGACAGGGAGCCCCAGGAGGGGCCUCCAGAGCAGCCCACAGGACCUGGCCAAGCUGCAGAGAAUGUCACCAUCCAGACUGUGUCCUAUGGGGUACAAGAGGAGCUGCGGGACCAGGAGGAUGACCAGGAGGAAGAGGAGAGCGAUGCCACUUCAACGGAGAGUGAAAGUGAAGACAACUUCCUCACGCUGCCUCCCAGGGACCACCUGGGACUUACUCUCUUCUCCAUGCUCUGCUGCUUCUGGCCACUGGGCAUUGCUGCCUUCUACUUCUCCCAGGGGACCAGCAAGGCCAUCUCCAAAGGGGACUUCCGCCUGGCCAGCACCACCUCCCGCCGGGCCCUCUUCCUAGCCACACUCGCCAUCGCCGUGGGGGCCGGUCUCUACGUGGCUGUGGUGGUGGCUCUGGCAGCUUACAUGUCCCAGAACGGUCAUGGCUAGUAGCCAGUAGGGCCUGCAUCCUGACUCCCCUGCCCACCUGAGGAAGCAGUGGGGCUUGGAGUUGCAGACCCUAUGGAAAGGCCCGGCCCCUGAAGAUGAUCCCGUGAGAGUGGCUUGCUGAGGGGGAGACCCCCAUUCCACAGCCUGCAGAGCUCAGCCUUCACUUCUGCUUGCCCGCUGCUCCCAGCCCCAGAGCAGGGCCCGGGGCGCCACUCUCUAACCCAGGCUACAGACGGGAAACAGAAGGCAGGGCUGCCCACCAGGCCAUCCCAGCAGGGCCUAGCUCCAUCCAUUCUGCCCAUUCCCUAGAGGAUCUCCUGCCCUACAGCCAGCCCACCACCUACCCUGCCAACCUCCCCACAGAGAAAGAGCAGGAGGUUACAGGGAGAAAAGGGGGUGCCCAGAGCACAAGGGGACCCGUCCCAAUCCUUUCAGCCCACAGGGAUCUUCACCUGGGGACAGCCUGAGCUUCCCCCAACUCCACUGUCUGGCCCCAUCAUGCCCAGACCUCAGCAGGCCAAGAAGGAAAUACGUGGAGGCAAGGGGGCCUCUUGCUGUCUCUGAUUCUAGAGGGUGCUUAUCUCUGCAUGGGCUUGUGAGGCACUGUAGAUUCUAGAUAGGGAAGAGGAGCCUCGGUAUGUAAACUCUGAACCAAGGGCAGGUUCUUGGAGCUUCUUCAUGCGGGUGCAAAAGGCAGUUGCAAUGACAGAGAAUAGAGGGUCCUGAAAUAUUGCUGUACUACAUGACUCUUCCUACUCUCCCCCCACUCCCCGCCCCUAUCAUCCUUUUCUGGGCUUUGCCUGGGGGUCCGUGAGCUGGUGCCAUCACAAGUAGACUAGACCCAGAGAGUGCCCUCAGCUCACCAGCCACUGAGCGCACGGCCCUAGGUCCAGCCCUACAGAAAACGCAGCAAGGAGAGACCCUAGGGAGUAGUGAGUAUAGAUGAGGGAAGGGACUCAGGGAAGGAAUGGCCUGCUGAGUAGUCAGCGGUGCUUAGGAAGGCUUCCUGGAGGAGGUAUCCCUUGAGCAAGUCCUAGGAUGAAUAGAAUUCAUCUAAGGGAUUUGGUCACAUAACUCUUUGUAUUUGUAGGCAGGGAUGUGGCAGGAACCUUCCAUGGGAAGCUUCCAGGCUGUUUGGAUUCUGCCUGGAACAUCUGGGCUGGAGCCAAACUACAGCCAUUCCUAAGGGUUCUGCCAACUCAAGGAGGAACGUCACACCUGUCUCUCAAAGACCAAUGAUGUUUUCCCAUCUCUGAAUGCUAGGGGGUCAGUGGUGGGUACCUGGUUACCCCUGGGGCAUCUUCACUGAUAUCUCUGCUCAGUGCCAGUCUCAACACCCUCAGCCACUAGGGCACAUCCAGAAUUUUAGAGACAUCUCCAGGUAGGCGGGGGGCAGCACCAAUGUGGGCAGGCCUGUCUGGACUCAAGCUACAGGCCCCUGCUGUGCAUGAUGUGGGAACCUGGUCAUUCCCAUGCCCCAUCCAGAGCCCAGGGCUGUGGCUCCACCACUGAGCAUCCCUUGUCCCACUGUCCUCCCCUGCCUCGGGCACUGCCCAGCCCUCCACUCCUGCAUCACAGCAGUUUUAAGGUCCCAUUAUUGUACUGAUUUAUCCUUGUAAUAAAUGUUUCUGUAACA